GAGACCCUGCGCGCGGCCGCCAGCGCUCCGGGAUCUCGAGAUAGCCGCAGCUCUCGCGAUCUUUCUGGAGCCGCACCUCCACGCGGAGUCCGAGCGCGUGUGCUGAGACCCCAGGGUCGGGAGGGCGGAGACUGGGAGGGAGGGAGAAGCCCCUUUGGCCUGCCUUACGGAAGCCUGCGAGGGAGGGUGGUGUCCACUGCCCAGUUCCGUGUCCCGAUGCCCAGCGCCAGCGCCAGCCGCAAGAGUCAGGAGAAGCCGCGGGAGAUCAUGGACGCGGCGGAAAUCGAGUUUUGGUUCGGGUUAGAGACUUGACAAUACAAAAAGCUGAUGAAGUUGUUUGGGUACGUGCAAGAGUUCAUACAAGCAGAGCUAAAGGGAAACAGUGCUUCUUAGUCCUACGUCAGCAGCAGUUUAAUGUCCAGGCUCUUGUGGCGGUGGGAGACCAUGCAAGCAAGCAGAUGGUUAAAUUUGCUGCCAACAUCAACAAAGAGAGCAUUGUGGAUGUAGAAGGUGUUGUGAGAAAAGUGAAUCAGAAAAUUGGAAGCUGUACACAGCAAGACGUUGAGUUACAUGUUCAGAAGAUUUAUGUGAUCAGUUUGGCUGAACCCCGUCUGCCCCUGCAGCUGGAUGAUGCUGUUCGGCCUGAGGCAGAAGGAGAAGAGGAAGGAAGAGCUACUGUUAACCAGGAUACAAGAUUAGACAACAGAGUCAUUGAUCUUAGGACAUCAACUAGUCAGGCAGUCUUCCGUCUCCAGUCUGGCAUCUGCCAUCUCUUCCGAGAAACUUUAAUUAACAAAGGUUUUGUGGAAAUCCAAACUCCUAAAAUUAUUUCAGCUGCCAGUGAAGGAGGAGCCAAUGUUUUUACUGUGUCAUAUUUUAAAAAUAAUGCAUACCUGGCUCAGUCCCCACAGCUAUAUAAGCAAAUGUGCAUUUGUGCUGAUUUUGAGAAGGUUUUCUCUAUUGGACCAGUAUUCAGAGCGGAAGACUCUAAUACCCAUAGACAUCUAACUGAGUUUGUUGGUUUGGACAUUGAAAUGGCUUUUAAUUACCAUUACCACGAAGUUAUGGAAGAAAUUGCUGACACCAUGGUACAAAUAUUCAAAGGACUUCAAGAAAGGUUUCAGACUGAAAUUCAAACAGUGAAUAAACAGUUCCCAUGUGAGCCAUUCAAAUUUUUGGAGCCAACUCUAAGACUAGAAUAUUGUGAAGCAUUGGCUAUGCUUAGGGAAGCUGGAGUCGAAAUGGGAGAUGAAGACGAUCUGAGCACACCAAAUGAAAAGCUGUUGGGUCAUUUGGUAAAGGAAAAGUAUGAUACAGAUUUUUAUAUUCUUGAUAAAUAUCCAUUGGCUGUAAGACCUUUCUAUACCAUGCCUGACCCAAGAAAUCCCAAACAGUCCAACUCUUACGAUAUGUUCAUGAGAGGAGAAGAAAUAUUGUCAGGAGCUCAAAGAAUACAUGAUCCUCAACUGCUAACAGAGAGAGCUUUACAUCAUGGAAUUGAUUUGGAGAAAAUUAAGGCUUACAUUGAUUCCUUCCGCUUUGGAGCCCCUCCUCAUGCUGGUGGAGGCAUUGGAUUGGAACGAGUUACUAUGCUGUUUCUGGGAUUGCAUAAUGUUCGUCAGACCUCCAUGUUCCCUCGUGAUCCCAAACGACUCACUCCUUAAAUUCACACUUUGCCACUUAACUCCAGUGUGGAUGACAGAGCGAGACCCUGCCUCAAAAAAAAAAAAAAAAAAAGAAAGCCACACUUAUUCUUUUCAGUAACCUGCUAGUGCACAGGCUGUACUUUAGGUACUUAAAAUAUGCACUAGAAUAAAUUUGCAAGGCCCUAAAAUAUCACUGUUAUUUUUGGAGUAAUUCAGUAUAGGUUCGUUUAAAAGAGAUUUUUAUAACUUCAGACAUGCAUCAGUAGGAAAUAACUUGAGAAAUUCAUAUGGUUAUGUUACAAAUUCAUAUUCUGUUACUACAGUAAACGUUAAGAGUUUUAAACAGUUAAGAUUGUACAAUUUUUCUUCUUUUCUAUAUUACAAGGGCCCCAGUGUUAAUGUCUUAGAUUUUCAGUAUUUGAACUUAUUUUUUUAAAUUCUGUCAUUGAGAUAAGAAUAAUUCAGGUAGCAUCUGAAAUUUUAAUGAAUGUAUAAUUGGCAUAUCAUGGAAAAUUAACCAGAAAGUAUCAGUUCUUAAAAGUUAUGCCUAGAAAUUAUGUAAAGCUAAACUACUGGUUAGAAAGUAUUCAGUGUAAUAUUGUAUUAAUUUGUUAAAUUCUAAACUUGAAUUUCAAUAAAAUUUUAAAGCUAAUUGUAGUUUUUGUGUAACUUUGUGGCCAACUGAUUUUGUAAGUGGUGCUAGGCAUUCAUAAUUUGGUAAAAGAAAAAAUACACAACUAGUUUAUAUAAAUAAAGACUAAUAUGUUGUCAACAUGUAUUCAUUUCAGGAUAUUAGUUUAGAUGGGCGUAGGGAUAGAGCUCUUAAAGUUGACAGCUUGGGUCGGUUGACAGAGUUCAUUUCACAUGGGUUAAAAUAUAUUGCAGAAUUUUGUUUGAUUUUUAACUGGAAUGGUACUGAUACUUAGUGAAUGUCAGUAAAAUCCAGUCCCAUCUUAUCCGUCAAAAAGAAAUUUUUGUGUAAGAAUUAGUUAGAAACACUUUCCCUCUAGAUUAUUACAAAUGUUGAUGCUAAUGUUAAUUUUACAUGACCACAAAUAUUGGGGAGGAACAAAACAUAACAUAUUUUUGUACAGGAAGAAAAAAUUACAUGCAGAAAAAUAUGAGGGUCAAAAAGUUAGGAAGUUACCCCUGGACCACGAACAUCUGCCCAUUAUGUUUGAAAGUUAAAGGGGGUGUUUACCAUCUAUAUUGUACAGUCUUUGAAAGUUUAGAUUCAGUUCUUAUUUUUUUCUUUCAUAUCCUACCAGAAUACCUUAAAUAUAGAAGGCACCCCAAAAGUAUUUCAUAAUUUAAUCCACAGCAAGAAUAAAAUAUCCAUCUUCUAUAGUGUGUAAUUGCUAGACCCUAAAAUAGUACAAUAAUAUUGGCCCUAGAGCUGUUCUUAAUUUCAUGUAAUUAUAGCUUGUUUCAAAAUAAAGUUUGUAAAGUCUUA